AUGAGUCAGUACAAGCAAGUUCACCUGACCUCUCAGCUGGGACCGCUGUCAGCAUCAUGAUUGGAGUACUGGCUGGGAUGGCUCUGAUAUAGCAGCCUUGGUGUAGUUUCUGCAUUUCGGGAAGAGUGUUUUUAUUAUCCACCUGCAGACUGGACUGGAUUCUUCUAGCUCCUUCAAUCCCAUUUUCUCCUGUGGCAUCACUAAGUAUAAGACCUGCUCUCUUCCUGAAGACCUAUAAGCUGGAGGUGGACAACUCAAUGUAAAUUUCAAGGAAAAACCCUCAUGCCUGAGAUGUGGGCCACUCAGAGCUAACCAAAAUGUUCAACACCAUAACUAGAGACACUCAAAUUGCCAACCAGGACAAGAAGUUGAUGACUUCAUGCUGUGGACAGUUUUUCCCAAGAUGUCCCAAGCCUCAUCGUGACGAGGCUCUUAUCCCACUCCAUUUUUCCCUGCUCAUGCCUGCCUCUUUAAUUUGGUAAGAUAAUGCUGUAACUAGAAUUUCACAAUCAGCGCCUUGUGCAGGUAAUUUGACAGAGUGUUGGAUGUGUCAUGUCAUCAUGUCAAACCCAAAUAUUUGACCUAAGGGAUCCUUUAUUCUGCCCAGUGGCUAACUUUAACAACAUCCCUAAUACAACUGUUUAUUCAAAUGCACGGUGGUCCCUGUUAGAGUUAGACCUCUAGACUCACCUGUUCUCACGCCCUGUUUUAAUUUAACCCAGCUAUGGGAUGCCAGAUAACAGAAUUGCUGCCUACUAGCUGAACAGGGAGGAGUUUGUGCAGUUGCUGACACUUCUUGUUGCACAUAAAUAAAUACAGUGGGUACUAUAGAGACUCAGUUGCAAAAAUUAACAAAUAUGCUGCUUGAUUAAAAUGGGUAGGCUUCUCAUGUGGCUCAUUCUUUAAUCUAUUCUCUUUUAUUUGGUUUGGUUCAUGGGGUCUCUGCCUAUGGAUCAUACUUCAAACUCUUGGUGUGAUCCUCCUGAUUGUCACAAUAUUAGUUACCCUGGUGUGCUGUAUUCUCUAAAACCUUUAAAUGUUUGCAUGCAGCCAUUCGUCAAAUGUCAAAUAUUCUCUCUUUGGCUGGAAUGACAAAAACUCAAAUAAAUGUAUGAUUAGGAGGACAUCAUAACCUAUGAAUGAUGGAAGUCCAAAAUGAUGGUAACUGACAGUAGUGUUAAUGCCUUAUGUUUAGUCAAACUCUCAUUUAGGUGACAGCCUGGUGACUCCAGAAUGGAGCCAGUCAUGCUAAAUGCCAUAUACUCACACUGAAACAUGAGGAAGCAGGUAGAUCCCAGAACAGACAAAAUUUUCCUAAAAACAUGAGAGUCCAGGCUGUCUGAGUCAGCACAGUAAGAAAGUCCUUUCUGCUUUAACUCUUAGAAAAAAGUAAUAUGAAGUAUUCUGAAAUUAACCAAUCAGUUUAUUUAAAUCAAUUUAUUUAUAUUCUUCUGUUCCUGGAUUCCCAUUUUACAAAACCCACUGUUCUACUGUUGUAUUGCCCAGUAGGAGCUAUCACUAUAUUUUGCAGAAUGGAAACUGCCCUGACUCAUGAAUCACAAAUAAAAGCCAAUUGUAUCUAUAA